GGAGUAUGAGCCACGCUCAGGGGAGCAGGUACCCCUUCUCCUAAAGAUGAAGAGGAGCAAACUGGCACUAAGCAAGGCCAUCGAGAGCGGGGACACUGACCUGGUGUUCACGGUGUUGCUGCACCUGAAGAACGAGCUGAACCGAGGAGAUUUUUUCAUGACCCUUCGGAAUCAGCCCAUGGCCCUCAGUUUGUACCGACAGUUCUGUAAGCAUCAGGAGCUAGAGACGCUGAAGGACCUUUACAAUCAGGAUGACAAUCACCAGGAAUUGGGCAGCUUCCACAUCCGAGCCAGCUAUGCUGCAGAAGAGCGUAUUGAGGGGCGAGUAGCAGCUCUGCAGACAGCCGCCGAUGCCUUCUACAAGGCCAAGAAUGAGUUUGCAGCCAAGGCUACAGAGGAUCAAAUGCGGCUCCUACGGCUGCAGCGGCGCCUAGAAGACGAGCUGGGGGGCCAGUUCCUAGACCUGUCUCUACAUGACACAGUUACCACCCUCAUUCUUGGCGGUCACAACAAGCGUGCAGAGCAGCUGGCACGUGACUUCCGCAUCCCUGACAAGAGGUGACACAACUAAAAAAAAACAAAGGUAUUUAUGGAAUUCCACUGAGUGGUAAUGGAUGAUGCAGUUCAAAUAACUAAGGACACAUGUUCAAAGAGCAUAAUUAACUUUUUAAAAGAAGCUAAUAAGCAUGGAUUCCUGGUUCAUUCUUGUUCUGCUCGGCAGUGGUCUGAUAUGUGUCAGUGCCAACAAUGCUACCACAGUUGCACCUUCUGUAGGAAUUACAAGAUUAAUUAACUCAUCAACGGCAGAACCAGUUAAAGAAGAGGCCAAAACUUCAAAUCCAACUUCUUCACUAACUUCUCUUUCUGUGGCACCAACAUUCAGCCCAAAUAUAACUCUGGGACCCACCUAUUUAACCACUGUCAAUUCUUCAGACUCUGACAAUGGGACCACAAGAACAGCAAGCACCAAUUCUAUAGGCAUUACAAUUUCACCAAAUGGAACGUGGCUUCCAGAUAACCAGUUCACGGAUGCCAGAACAGAACCCUGGGAGGGGAAUUCCAGCACCGCAGCAACCACUCCAGAAACUUUCCCUCCUUCAGGUAAUUCUGACUCGAAGGACAGAAGAGAUGAGACACCAAUUAUUGCGGUGAUGGUGGCCCUGUCCUCUCUGCUAGUGAUCGUGUUUAUUAUCAUAGUUUUGUACAUGUUAAGGUUUAAGAAAUACAAGCAAGCUGGGAGCCAUUCCAAUUCUUUCCGCUUAUCCAACGGCCGCACUGAGGAUGUGGAGCCCCAGAGUGUGCCACUUCUGGCCAGAUCCCCAAGCACCAACAGGAAAUACCCACCCCUGCCCGUGGACAAGCUGGAAGAGGAAAUUAACCGGAGAAUGGCAGACGACAAUAAGCUCUUCAGGGAGGAAUUCAACGCUCUCCCUGCAUGUCCUAUCCAGGCCACCUGUGAGGCUGCUUCCAAGGAGGAAAACAAGGAAAAAAAUCGAUAUGUAAACAUCUUGCCUUAUGACCACUCUAGAGUCCACCUGACACCGGUUGAAGGGGUUCCAGAUUCUGAUUACAUCAAUGCUUCAUUCAUCAACGGCUACCAAGAAAAGAACAAAUUCAUUGCUGCACAAGGACCAAAAGAAGAAACGGUGAAUGAUUUCUGGCGGAUGAUCUGGGAACAAAACACAGCCACCAUCGUCAUGGUUACCAACCUGAAGGAGAGAAAGGAGUGCAAGUGCGCCCAGUACUGGCCAGACCAAGGCUGCUGGACCUAUGGGAAUAUUCGGGUGUCUGUAGAGGAUGUGACUGUCCUGGUGGACUACACAGUACGGAAGUUCUGCAUCCAGCAGGUGGGCGACAUGACCAACAGAAAGCCACAGCGCCUCAUCACUCAGUUCCACUUUACCAGCUGGCCAGACUUUGGGGUGCCUUUUACCCCGAUCGGCAUGCUCAAGUUCCUCAAGAAGGUGAAGGCCUGUAACCCUCAGUAUGCAGGGGCCAUCGUGGUCCACUGCAGUGCAGGUGUAGGGCGUACAGGUACCUUUGUCGUCAUUGAUGCCAUGCUGGACAUGAUGCAUACAGAACGGAAGGUGGACGUGUAUGGCUUUGUGAGCCGGAUCCGGGCACAGCGCUGCCAGAUGGUGCAAACCGAUAUGCAGUAUGUCUUCAUAUACCAAGCCCUUCUGGAGCAUUAUCUCUAUGGAGAUACAGAACUGGAAGUGACCUCUCUAGAAACCCACCUGCAGAAAAUUUACAACAAAAUCCCAGGGACCAGCAACAAUGGAUUAGAGGAGGAGUUUAAGAAGUUAACAUCAAUCAAAAUCCAGAAUGACAAGAUGCGGACUGGAAACCUUCCAGCCAACAUGAAGAAGAACCGUGUUUUACAGAUCAUUCCAUAUGAAUUCAACAGAGUGAUCAUUCCAGUUAAGCGGGGCGAAGAGAAUACAGACUAUGUGAACGCAUCCUUUAUUGAUGGCUACCGGCAGAAGGACUCCUAUAUCGCCAGCCAGGGCCCUCUUCUCCACACAAUUGAGGACUUCUGGCGAAUGAUCUGGGAGUGGAAAUCCUGCUCUAUCGUGAUGCUAACAGAACUGGAGGAGAGAGGCCAGGAGAAGUGUGCCCAGUACUGGCCAUCUGAUGGACUGGUGUCCUAUGGAGAUAUUACAGUGGAACUGAAGAAGGAGGAGGAAUGUGAGAGCUACACCGUCCGAGACCUCCUGGUCACCAACACCAGGGAGAAUAAGAGCCGGCAGAUCCGGCAGUUCCACUUCCAUGGCUGGCCUGAAGUGGGCAUCCCCAGUGACGGAAAGGGCAUGAUCAGCAUCAUCGCCGCCGUGCAGAAGCAGCAGCAGCAGUCAGGGAACCACCCCAUCACCGUGCACUGCAGCGCCGGGGCAGGAAGGACGGGGACCUUCUGUGCCCUGAGCACCGUCCUGGAGCGUGUGAAAGCAGAGGGGAUUUUGGAUGUCUUCCAGACUGUCAAGAGCCUGCGGCUACAGAGGCCACACAUGGUCCAGACACUGGAACAGUAUGAGUUCUGCUACAAGGUGGUGCAGGAGUAUAUUGAUGCAUUCUCAGAUUAUGCCAACUUCAAGUAAGCGGCAACAAGGGUCCGUGGACCAGGAGGAUUGCCUUUAAUAUUUUGUAAUAUUCUGUUUUGUUAAUAUACCCCAAAUUGUGUAUAUAUCUUAUAACUGUUUUAGAAAUUGGUACAUAGGCUUCUAUUACCUAUUAGGUGGAAAUUUUAUAUGUAAAUGUGUUAGCACUGAUAGUCCUUUUUCCAAUGUUUUAUUGGGGAAUUAAAUAGUGUGAUGUUUGGAUUGAUAUCGUGAAAUCCUCAGCCGAGAAAUUGGGCUGGAUUGUGCUUUGGUUAAUACAUCUUUCCCUAAAGAAGAUAAACACAAAAUCCAUUCCAGGUAGCUCGGCACCAACUAAGAAAAAAAGCACAAAGUUCUCAGAGCUCUCGAGGAAAGUGGUUGUCCCCGUACCACCAUGCACUGUAAAUAUCCCUCCCCUCUCUCCCUGGUCCCCUCCCCCAUCCCCACCACUGAUAUCAUGGGGAGUAAUAGGACCAGAGCGGUAUCUCUGGCACCACACUAGGGACUAUCAGGUAAUAAAAGCUUUGACUCCCUGA